GCGGCUGCGUCAGGGAUUCCUUGGUGGCCCUGGAGGGUGGAUAGGCUGGCCUGGGGGCCAUCAGGACAGCAGGUGACGGUCAGGCCAAUGCCAGCCGGGCCUGGGCACAGCCCUGUGGGGGCUUCGGAGGGCCCUGAGGAGGAGGAGGAAGAGGCAGAGGAGAGAAGGCCCCACGGAGGUCCUGUCGCCAGCGCUGCCACUGCCUGACCUCCGCUGCCCGAAGGCCGGUGGGCCUCUGUGGCCUCCGUGAAGCAGGCCCGGCUGUCGUCAGGCCAUGUCUGGUCCAUGGCCCUCCCCCGACAGCCGGACCAAGGGAACGGUGGCCUGGCUGGCGGAGGUACUCCUCUGGGUUGGAGGGAGUGUGGUGCUGUCUUCAGAGUGGCAGCUCGGCCCCCUGGGUAAGAAGGGGCAGGCGAGUGGCCUGGGCUGAGUGCUGGCCCUGGCCAGGUGACUGGUGGGUGGGGGCUGUUCCUGGAGGUGGGGGAAGCCUGGGCCUCCAUCCCAUCCUGCACUCGCCUCCCCUGUCCCCCGGGUGCUCUAGGGAUCAUGUGGGUCCAGCAGCGUCGGCUGGCCCUGCCCCUCAGCCGCUCAGAGGCGUGCUCAGCACACCUCGGUCUCCCAGGCACCUGCAGGGCCUGGGGGCUGAACCCAAGGGGGCGAGGGGGGAUCUCAGGUGGCUCCAAUGCUCUCAUUGAAGGGGUGCCUUGUGCUCUGGGGGUCAGUGGUGCUUGCAGCCCAGGCGGCUGGGCUGGCAUCCUGGUGCCGGACAUGAGGGCCUUUGCCGUUAGGAGACUCUGCAGAGGAGACUGGCUGGGUAUGGCUGGGAGGGUGGAGUGUGUGUCUUGUGGUGGCCUGUGGAGGGCCCCGGUCCGGGCUGGCCUGCCAGCUCUCUGUUCCAGCGGCAGACAGGGUCCUGUCCAGGCUGCCCUGUUGCAGGCCUCUGCCCGCCCCCUGCCCCUGUGUCCUGCCUCACCCCUCUCCUAAAUCCCUGCAGCCAUACCUGCGUCUUCACCUCCCAUGUGCCCCGGAGAGCCCAGCCCCCCAUGCCAUGGCUUCCAUCCCUUCAAUUCCCCUCUGCUCGUGAUCACGUAGUAGCUUCCCCAAGAAGGCCCGGCCAGUACUGCCCUUGGUCCUCUACAACGCCCCCGCCAGGGUCCCUCAGCGUGCAGACCUGGGGUGGGGAUUAACGUCUCUGUGCUUUAGCAGAUGGUACCUCUGGGACCCGGGCUUUCUGUGAGCAGGUGUGCAGGAACCGAGGGGGUGAGACCAGUCUGUUCCUGGGCUGGGACAGCUGACUCUGGCCUGGACUCCCUGGACCCUGCAGCCCCCUCUCCUGGGACAAGCUACAGCAGGAGGCUGAAUGGAGAGAGGAGGGGAGAGAAGGAGCGAGUGGAGCGGUGCAUGGGUGCCAUGCAAGAGGGGAUGCAGAUGGUGAAGCUGCGUGGCGGCUCCAAGGGCCUGGUCCGCUUCUACUACCUGGACGAGCACCGCUCCUGCAUCCGCUGGAGGCCCUCACGCAAGAACGAGAAGGCCAAGAUCUCCAUCGACUCCAUCCAGGAGGUGAGUGAGGGGCGGCAGUCGGAGGUCUUCCAGCGCUACCCUGACGGCAGCUUCGACCCCAACUGCUGCUUCAGCAUCUACCACGGCAGCCACCGCGAGUCGCUGGACCUGGUCUCCACCAGCAGCGAGGUGGCGCGCACCUGGGUCACUGGCCUGCGCUACCUCAUGGCCGGCAUCAGCGACGAGGACAGCCUGGCUCGCCGCCAGCGCACCAGGGACCAGUGGCUGAAGCAGACGUUUGACGAGGCCGACAAGAACGGGGAUGGCAGCCUGAGCAUUGGCGAGGUCCUGCAGCUGCUGCACAAGCUCAACGUGAACCUGCCCCGGCAGAGGGUGAAGCAGAUGUUCAGGGAAGCGGACACGGAUGACCACCAAGGGACGCUGGGUUUUGAAGAGUUCUGUGCCUUCUACAAGAUGAUGUCCACCCGCCGGGACCUCUACCUGCUCAUGCUGACCUACAGCAACCACAAGGACCACCUGGAUGCCGCCAGCCUGCAGCGCUUCCUGCAGGUGGAGCAGAAGAUGGCGGGUGUGACCCUCGAGAGCUGCCAGGACAUCAUCGAGCAGUUUGAGCCAUGCCCAGAAAACAAGAGUAAGGGGCUGCUGGGCAUUGAUGGCUUCACCAACUACACCAGGAGCCCUGCUGGUGACAUCUUCAACCCUGAGCACCACCAUGUGCACCAGGACAUGACGCAGCCGCUGAGCCACUACUUCAUCACCUCGUCCCACAACACCUACCUCGUGGGUGACCAGCUCAUGUCCCAGUCACGGGUGGACAUGUAUGCUUGGGUCCUGCAGGCUGGCUGCCGCUGCGUGGAGGUGGACUGCUGGGAUGGGCCCGACGGGGAGCCCAUUGUGCACCAUGGCUACACUCUGACUUCCAAGAUCCUCUUCAAAGACGUCAUUGAAACCAUCAACAAAUAUGCCUUCAUCAAGAAUGAGUACCCAGUGAUCCUGUCCAUCGAAAACCACUGCAGUGUCAUCCAGCAGAAGAAAAUGGCCCAGUAUCUGACUGACAUCCUUGGGGACAAGCUGGACCUGUCAUCAGUGAGCAGUGAAGAUGCCACCACACUCCCCUCUCCACAGAUGCUCAAGGGCAAGAUCCUCGUGAAGGGGAAGAAGCUCCCAGCCAACAUCAGCGAGGAUGCGGAGGAAGGCGAGGUGUCUGAUGAGGACAGUGCUGAUGAGAUUGACGAUGACUGCAAGCUCCUCAAUGGGGAUGCAUCCACCAAUCGAAAGCGUGUAGAAAACACUGCUAAGAGGAAACUGGAUUCCCUCAUCAAAGAGUCGAAGAUUCGGGACUGUGAGGACCCCAACAACUUCUCCGUCUCCACACUGUCCCCAUCUGGAAAGCUCGGACGCAAGAGCAAGGCUGAAGAGGACGUGGAGUCUGGGGAGGAUGCCGGGGCCAGCAGACGCAAUGGCCGCCUCGUCGUGGGAAGCUUCUCCAGGCGCAAGAAGAAGGGCAGCAAGCUGAAGAAGGCGGCCAGCGUGGAGGAGGGAGAUGAGGGUCAGGACUCCCCGGGAGGCCAGAGCCGAGGGGCGACCCGGCAGAAGAAGACCAUGAAGCUGUCCCGGGCCCUCUCUGACCUGGUGAAGUACACCAAGUCCGUGGCCACCCACGACAUAGAGAUGGAGGCGGCGUCCAGCUGGCAGGUGUCGUCCUUCAGCGAGACCAAGGCCCACCAGAUUCUGCAGCAGAAGCCGGCGCAGUACCUACGCUUCAACCAGCAGCAGCUCUCCCGCAUCUACCCCUCCUCCUACCGUGUGGACUCCAGCAACUACAACCCGCAGCCCUUCUGGAACGCCGGCUGCCAAAUGGUUGCCCUGAACUACCAGUCAGAGGGGCGGAUGCUGCAGCUGAACCGAGCCAAGUUCAGCGCCAACGGUGGCUGCGGCUACGUACUCAAGCCUGGGUGCAUGUGCCAGGGCGUGUUCAACCCCAACUCGGAGGACCCCCUGCCCGGGCAGCUCAAGAAGCAGCUGGUGCUCCGGAUCAUCAGUGGCCAGCAGCUUCCCAAGCCGCGCGACUCCAUGCUGGGGGACCGUGGGGAGAUCAUCGACCCCUUUGUGGAGGUGGAGAUCAUUGGGCUCCCUGUGGACUGCAGCAGGGAGCAGACCCGCGUGGUGGACGACAACGGGUUCAACCCCACCUGGGAGGAGACCCUGGUUUUCAUGGUGCACAUGCCGGAGAUCGCGCUGGUCCGCUUCCUCGUCUGGGACCACGAUCCCAUCGGGCGUGACUUCAUUGGCCAGAGGACGCUGGCCUUCAGCAGCAUGAUGCCAGGCUACAGACACGUGUACCUAGAAGGGAUGGAAGAGGCCUCCAUCUUCGUGCAUGUGGCUGUCAGUGACAUCAGCGGUAAGGUCAAGCAGGCUCUGGGCCUAAAAGGCCUCUUCCUCCGAGGCCCAAAGCCCGGCUCGCUGGACAGUCAUGCUGCUGGGCGGCCCCCGGCCCGGCCCUCCGUUAGCCAGCGGAUCCUGCGGCGCACGGCCAGCGCCCCGACCAAGAGCCAGAAGCCGGGCCGCAGGGGCUUCCCGGAGCUGGUCCUGGGUACACGGGACACAGGCUCCAAGGGGGUGGCAGACGAUGUGGUGCCCCCCGGGCCCGGACCUGCUCCGGAAGCCCCAGCCCAGGAGGGGCCCGGCAGCGGCAGCCCCCGAGCGGCCACUCCCCCCACUGUGCAGCCUGGAAACCAUCGCUGAGGAGCCCGCCCCAGGCCCUGGUCCCCCGCCACCAGCGGCUGUCCCCACCAGCUCUUCUCAGGGACGGCCCCCAUACCCCACAGGACCCGGAGCCAAUGUGGCAAGCCCCCUAGAGGACACUGAGGAGCCCCGAGACAGCAGGCCUCGGCCGUGCAACGGCGAGGGCGCCGGCGGGGCAUACGAGAGGGCCCCCGGCAGCCAGACGGACGGCAGGAGCCAGCCCCGGACCCUGGGCCACCUGCCCGUGAUUAGAAGGGUGAAGAGUGAGGGGCAGGUGCCCACGGAGCCCCUGGGAGGGUGGCGGCCCCUGGCCGCUCCCUUUCCAGCUCCUGCCGUGUACUCCGAUGCCACGGGCAGUGACCCGCUGUGGCAGCGGCUGGAGCCAUGUGGCCACCGAGACAGCGUUUCCUCCUCCUCCAGCAUGUCAUCCAGCGACACUGUCAUUGACCUCUCCCUGCCCAGCCUGGGCCUGGGCCGCAGCCGUGAGAACCUCGCUGGAGCCCACAUGGGACGCCUGCCCCCCAGGCCCCACUCGGCUUCGGCUGCCCGCCCAGACCUGCCACCUGUGACCAAGAGCAAAUCCAACCCCAACCUUCGGGCUACAGGCCAGCGGCCUCCCAUACCUGACGAACUGCAGCCCAGGUCCCUGGCCCCAAGGAUGGCUGGCCUCCCCUUCCGGCCUCCCUGGGGCUGCCUUUCCCUGGUGGGCGUGCAGGACUGCCCCGUGGCUGCCAAGUCCAAGAGCCUGGGCGACCUCACUGCUGAUGACUUUGCCCCUAGCUUUGAGGGCGGCUCCCGCAGACUGAGCCACAGCCUGGGCCUCCCGGGAGGGACACGGCGGGUGUCGGGGCCAGGGGUGAGACGGGACACCCUGACAGAGCAGCUGCGCUGGCUCACUGUCUUCCAGCAGGCAGGAGACAUCACGUCACCCACCAGCCUGGGCCCGGCUGGGGAGGGGGUGGCAGGGGGCCCUGGUUUUGUGCGGCGCUCCUCCUCCCGCAGCCACAGCCGCGUGCGUGCCAUUGCCAGCCGGGCCCGCCAGGCCCAGGAGCGGCAGCAGAGACUGCAGGGCCUGGGCCGGCAGGGACCCCCAGAAGAGGAGCGGGGCACCCCCGAGGGCGCCUGCUCCGUGGGCCACGAGGGCAGUGUGGAUGCACCAGCACCCUCCAAGGGAGCCCUCGGGCCAGCAUCCGCGGCUGCUGAAAACCUGGUCCUGCUCCGCCUCUGACCGUCAGUGGUGGGAACCUGGGCGGCUCUGGAGGCCCAGGGCAGGGGUGGGCGUGUUGUUUGCUCAGGAAACAGGGCAGCCAGGCCCCCAAAACUGUGUCCCCCUGGCUGCCCUGUGUCCCCUCCACCCCUGCCUCCCUCCUGCCCCUGCUCCCGGGGAGGAAAGGCUAAAGCUGCUGGCCCGGGGCCCACAGGAGGGGCUUCGAGGCUGGCCCUGCCAGGCAGUUUUCCCGGCGUUUUAGGAUCUGUACAUAGAGAAAUAUUUAAAUUUUUAGAAGCAAAACUUAUACAACAUUAAAAUGAUACCAAGUCCCUUUC